GAAGCUGCCUCCGCCAUCUUGGAGAUGGGAGACGGGCGAUGGCUGUGGUCCUUCUGCUAAUGCAAACAACAAAACGGGCACACUAGUCACCCCCGAGGGAGGCCACCAUCACUGUAACUGUUGGCCAAAGCUACAAAAGAAGCGAGGGAAUCCAACCGAGCGCAGCGACACUGAGAACAGCUUCCCCUGCCUUCUGCGGCGGCAGAAGUGAAGUGCCUGAGGACCGGAAGGAUGGUGCAGUCCUGCUCCGCCUACGGCUGCAAGAACCGCUACGACAAGGACAAGCCCGUUUCUUUCCACAAGUUUCCUCUUACUCGACCCAGUCUUUGUAAAGAAUGGGAGGCAGCUGUCAGAAGAAAAAACUUUAAACCCACCAAGUAUAGCAGUAUUUGUUCAGAGCACUUUACUCCAGACUGCUUUAAGAGAGAGUGCAACAACAAGUUACUGAAAGAGAAUGCUGUGCCCACAAUAUUUCUUUGUACUGAGCCACAUGACAAGAAAGAAGAUCUUCUGGAGCCACAGGAACAGCUUCCCCCACCUCCUUUACCGCCUCCUGUUUCCCAGGUUGAUGCUGCUAUUGGAUUACUAAUGCCGCCUCUUCAGACCCCUGUUAAUCUCUCAGUUUUCUGUGACCACAACUAUACUGUGGAGGAUACAAUGCACCAGCGGAAAAGGAUUCAUCAGCUAGAACAGCAAGUUGAAAAACUCAGAAAGAAGCUCAAGACCGCACAGCAGCGAUGCAGAAGGCAAGAACGGCAGCUUGAAAAAUUAAAGGAGGUUGUUCACUUCCAGAAAGAGAAAGACGACGUAUCAGAAAGAGGUUAUGUGAUUCUACCAAAUGACUACUUUGAAAUAGUUGAAGUACCAGCAUAAAAAAAUGAAAUGUGUAUUGAUUUCUAAUGGGGCAAUACCACAUAUCCUCCUCUAGCCUGUAAAGGAGUUUCAUUUAAAAAAAUAACAUUUGAUUACUUAUAUAAAAACAGUUCAGAAUAUUUUUUUAAAAAAAAUUCUAUAUAUACUGUAAAAUUAUAAAUUUUUUUGUUUGUAAUUUCAGGUUUUUUACAUUUUAACAAAAUAUUUUAAAAGUUAUAAACUAACCUCAGACCUCUAAUGUAAGUUGGUUUCAAGAUUGGGGAUUUUGGGGUUUUUUUUUAGUAUUUAUAGAAAUAAUGUAAAAAUAAAAAGUAAAGAGAAUGAGAACAGUGUGGUAAAAGGGUGAUUUCAGUUUAAAACUUAAAAUUAGUACUGUUUUAUUGAGAGAAUUUAGUUAUAUUUUAAAUCAGAAGUAUGGGUCAGAUCAUGGGACAUAACUUCUUAGAAUAUAUAUAUACAUAUGUACAUAUUCUCAUAUGUAAAGUCACAAGGUUCAUUUAUCUUUCUGAAUCAGUUAUCAAAGAUAAAUUGGCAAGUCAGUACUUAAGAAAAAAGAUUUGAUUAUCAUCACAGCAGAAAAAAGUCAUUGCAUAUCUGAUCAAUAACUUCAGAUUCUAAGAGUGGAUUUUUUUUUUUUACAUGGGCUCCUAUUUUUUCCCCUACUGUCUUGCAUUAUAAAAUUAGAAGUGUAUUUUCAGUGGAAGAAACAUUUUUCAAUAAAUAAAGUAAGGCAUUGUCAUCAAUGAAGUAAUUAAAACUGGGACCUGAUCUAUGAUACGCUUUUUUCUUUCAUUACACCCUAGCUGAAGGACAUCCAGUUCCCCAGCUGUAGUUAUGUAUCUGCCUUCAAGUCUCUGACAAAUGUGCUGUGUUAGUAGAGUUUGAUUUGUAUCAUAUGAUAAUCUUGCACUUGACUGAGUUGGGACAAGGCUUCACAUAAAAAAUUAUUUCUUCACUUUUAACACAAGUUAGAAAUUAUAUCCCAUUUAGUUAAGUGCGUGAUUUAUAUUCAGAACAACCUACUAUGUAGCGUUUAUUUUACUGAAUGUGGAGAUUUAAACACUGAGGUUUCUGUUCAAACUGUGAGUUCUGUUCUUUGUGAGAAAUUUUACAUAUAUUGGAAGUGAAAAUAUGUUCUGAGUAAACAAAUAUUGCUAUGGGAGUUAUCUUUUUAGAUUUAGAAUAACUGUUCCAAUGAUAAUUAUUACUUUUAUAUUUCAAAGUACACUAAGAUCGUUGAAGAGCAAUAGAACCUUUAAGACAGUAUUAAAGGUGUGAAACAAUGGCA